GCGGAAGCGCUGCCAGGCGUCCGGAGCGGAGCUUCCAGGGUCUCUGGGUCGCCAGCGCGCGGGCGCGCGGCUGGAGCCGGCGCCGGGCACGGCAUCGGGGGCCUGGACUGCACGGCCCGGCAGCAGGCCGGCCAUGGAGCCAGGCAGCGUGGAGAACCUGUCCAUCGUGUACCGGAGCCGCGACUUCCUGGUGGUCAACAAGCACUGGGACGUUCGCAUUGACAGCAAGGCGUGGCGGGAGACUCUGACCCUGCAGAAGCAGCUGCGGUACCGCUUUCCCGAGCUGGCCGACCCUGACACCUGCUACGGGUUCAGGUUCUGCCACCAGCUGGAUUUCUCCACCAGCGGGGCGCUGUGCGUGGCCCUAAACAAGGCAGCCGCCGGCAGCGCGUACAGGUGCUUCAAGGAGCGGCGCGUGACCAAGGCUUACCUGGCAUUGGUGGGCUCCCCGGCAGCACUGGGCUGCCCCGUGAACUGCGUGCGAUUCUCCCUCUCCUGCAGCUGCGGGGGCACAUCCAGGAGAGCCGGGUAACCAUCAGCCAUGCCAUUGGCAGGAACAGCACGGAGGGCCGGGCCCACACCAUGUGCAUCGAGGGCUCGCAGGGUUGUGAGAACCCAAAGCCAAGCCUCACAGAUCUCGUGGUUCUGGAACACGGGCUGUACGCAGGCGAUCCUGUCUCCAAAGUGCUGCUGAAGCCGCUCACGGGCCGGACACACCAGCUGCGCGUGCACUGCAGUGCCCUGGGCCACCCCGUGGUGGGCGACCUGACCUACGGAGAAGUCUCGGGCCGGGAGGACCGGCCGUUCAGAAUGAUGCUGCACGCUUUCUACCUGCGCAUCCCCACGGACACCGAGUGUGUGGAGGUCUGCACGCCUGACCCCUUCCUGCCCUCCCUGGAUGCCUGCUGGAGCCCCCACACACUGCUGCAGUCGCUGGACCAGCUCGUGCAGGCCUUACGGGCCACCCCCGACCCUGACCCCGAGGAUAGGGGCCCCAGGCCAGGCAGCCCCUCCGCACUCCUGCCUGGGCCCGGCCGGCCUCCUCCACCCCCAACCAAGCCCCCUGAGACUGAGGCACAGCGGGGCCCCUGCCUGCAGUGGCUGUCGGAGUGGACGCUGGAACCGGACAGCUGAGAGCCGUGGGGCUGGGGCAGGGGGUGUCAGCUGCACAGCGGGACUCUAGGGAGAUGGGCGAGCGAGCGUCUGCUCACUGGCUCUGGGGCCUCGAGGUGCCAGGCAGCAUCAGGCCCACUGGGUUGCCCCGGCCAGGCCUGCGAGGAAGGGCUGAGGUGGGGCCGGCAGGGGGCGCCAGGCAGCCGUGAUCACAGGUGACGACCGCACCGCGGCCGUGGGACUGAUGCGGGAUCCCGAGGGCCUUCCUGCCCACAUGCCCCGGGAGAAACCGAGGCCCCUCCCUCCUCCUGGAACAGCUUCCGGCUCUCAAGCGUCACCCCAGGGGCGUCAGUUUUACGGACUCAAGGUCACCUCAGGAAGAGGCAGGGCCAGGUUUUGGGAUAGGCUUUGCCUCCAGGAUGGGCUGCUCCUGGGCCUGGUGAGCUACUGCCCCCAACCUACCCUCUAGAGGGGCUGGGAAGGGCCGUUCUGGGCUCACCUGGCCUGGGAGACCCAUCUGGUCCCUGCGUCCUCUGCCCCUCACUGCUCUGUGCAGAUCCUGUCGCCCUCAGCUGCCUCCUCCCGAGACCUAAUGGUCCCUGCUGGGCUCGAGUCUGCAGGCCCGGCUGCGUGUGCCUUGGCCUCACUGUACCAGUGGUUCCCUCUCUGCCCGGAUUCUGAGCUCAGUGUGGUGUUUGGUGCACAGGGGUUGGUCAGGGGCCAUGGCCAAGGCCCUGCCACGCACGCCCAUCCCUCAGAUCCACUGUGAGCACCAACCUGCUGCAGUCUCUUGGGCCCCUGCUGGCAGCUCUGCCACGUCACCGCCUGCCUGGCUCCCACACAGCCAUGCAUUGUCACUCUGCCUCCGGGACCCCAGCUUGGGAGCUGUGGGUCUGCCAGGUCCCACCUCCUCUGUCCCCCAUGCCACAACCUGGGCUCCUGGCUACAGCAGGGCUCCAGGGACUCCAAAUAAAUGUUCAGUGACUGGCUCCAAGGA